UGUAUAGGUGAGGGCUACUGUGCAGGUAGUUGUGUUGCCCCAGUUUCAUUAUAAAACACAUAAAACUUGAAUCACUGACCUCACCCAUAACCGUUGAAUUGCUUUUUGGUGGUGGAAGCCGUGACCCAGAACAGUGCUGAGGUGUCCUUUGUCCUUGGUACUGGCAUUGUCAGAUAGUGUUUGGGCUCCCGCGUGGUCUCCAGUGGUUUCUCUAAGAACCAUGGUCCCUACAGAAAAAUGACCACUGACUACCAGCAGGGUUAGCAAAUGGCUGUGGUGAAAUAAGCACAUAACUUAUAUAUAAGUUACACAACUCUGAGAUCAGAUGAGUGGCCUUGCCGGGGCAGAACUUUCAGAGAGAAAAUGAAAUGUUCUGGUGCAGCCCAGAAUGCUGCUUUCCGUUCAGAGAGUGCCUCGCCUUGCAUAUUCUGAGAAUCCUUCUCUUAGGUGGCCUCAUUAAUUCCAUUCUCCUUGAAGGAAACAGUUGACAAGCCCAGAGUCUGAAGCUGGGCUCCCUGGCCUCUAACUUGUCCUGCUGACCUCUUCUGGGAGAGGAAAAACUUUGCUUCUACCCUCGUAGGUUCUGUUUUGGGGGACCUGGGAAUUAAACUGACAAAAGACAGACUAGCAAGAGAAAAGACAGAUUUCACCACUUAUGUACGAGAGGUCAUAGAAAAGUGUCCCUCAAAGGGGCAUUUAGAAUUCUGGGCUUAUGCACCGUCCGUCCUUCACAGGGGAAGGGGAGUGAGAGAAAGGUACCUGUGGGCAAACGAAUGGCUUUUUGGAAAGACAAGUGGGCCCUCAAGAGAACAGAGAACAGAUGGGCGAUGUGGUAGUUUUGUGAUCAUUCCUGUUUCAGUGCAGUGUGGAGGCUUCUCAUCUCCAGUGGUAAGAGUCCUGUUUCCCUGGCCCCUCCUAAGGGACAGGAUUUAUAGCAGAUGGAUUCUUUUGACUUCUUUUGGGGAACUCUGCUUUUCAGUAGCUAAGAGAAUUCAGGAACGCAAAUGCCUUCUGCUCAAAAUGAUUUUGAUGCCACAGCGGCAGAUUCUGGGCCCAUUCAUCUCCUCCACGCCAACCCCCUGGCAGCCCCCAGCCCUGUGCAGCUUCUCAGCCCUGCUGGUUGGUGGAGCAUCCACAGGGUGUCUCAGGUUUGAUUUGAGGGCAUCUGUGUUCUUCAACCAGAUUGCUUCUCUUCUUGACUUAUUUCAUGUCUGCUGUGAGUCUAGCCACAAGUGCCUGAACACUUAGGUUUUAUUUAGUGAAUGUCUAGCUUCUUCAUUUUGUAAGUUUAUUUUGAUAUAAUUUCAAACUCACGUAACUUACUAACAUCUGUAAGAAUGUUCCUGUAGAACCGCUGUAUGUCAAAGAUUAACAUUUAGCCUCAUCUGCUUCUCUCCCUGCCCCUCCACAGUGUGUUUGUGUGUGUGUGUGUGUGUGCAUGUGUGUAGAUGUAUGUUUGUACACACACACUUUUCUGAACCACUUGAGAGUAAGUUGCAGACAUCAUACCCUCUUAUUUGUAAAUACUUCCGUGUGUAUUUCCUAUGAAUAAGACAUUCUCUUAUAAAACCACAGCAAAAAGAUCAAAAUCAGGAAAUUUAACACCGAUAAGAUACUGUUAUCUAACCCACAGUCCAUGUUAAAAACAAUAUCAAAUGUCAAAUAUCUGUGAUAGCAUUUCUUCUUCUGUUCAGGAUCUAGUUCGGGUUCAUACAUUGCGUUUAAUUAUCCUAUGGGUCUCGUCUCUUCAUCUAGCACUGUUCCUCGGCCUUUUUUCAUCUUUUCUGACCUUGGCUUUUUUUCCUUCUUCUUCUGAGACAAUGGCCUUGUUGUGUUUGAAGAGUUCAAGCCACUUAUUUUAUAGAAUGUGCCACAUUUUAACUUUGUUAUUUCCUCAUCCUCAUGAUUAGAUUCAGAUUAUGCAUUUUUGACAGAAAUCCCAUAGAAAUGAGGCAGCUUUCUCUUUAAUGGAGAAGGAGCUAUAGGCAUGGGAAGAGGGAGGGGAACUGGAAGGAACUGAGUGAGGUUGGAUUGGAAUGAAAGUUCUCGGGAUAAACUGGUGAUGGUCGAUAUAGAAAUAGAGAAGGGUGUGUGUGUGCGUGUGUGUGGGUGUGUGUGUGUAAAAUGCACCCCGCUAGGAGGUCCUGGGAACAGUAAGAGCACUAAAGUGAGCACACUUUGGUCCGGGAUCUUGGUUUCUGCAUGGCAUCUCCCACUAAAAGGAGCCAGGAGUCCUUGGAGACCUGGCCAAUGCCAGGACUGGGGCAGGGCAAGGAAUAGAUGAGCCCAGAACAUCUUGUGCCAGAAAAUAAGGAAGUACUUACAAACAAAGGGACUCUGACUUGUCAAAUCUAGGACAAUCUGAGAUUUACAAUAAAUGAGACUCAUGAAUGAUAGCCCAUUGAAUAGCGUAAGAUUCGGCGAGUCCUACUGAUAUAACUAAAGAAGUAGGAGAAAUGCACGCUCGCCGUACAGUGGAAGCUGGCCGCUAGGUGGAGCGGGGAUGUGGAGCCGCUGCAGGGUACCCAGCGCAGGCACAGAACGCCAUGGAUGCACCCCGUGGGGCGGCAGCUUGAGGAACAGGAUAUCUACAUUAUCUCAAAGCAGGUUCCCAGAAAUUCCAUAUUCAUUACUUAGAGGGAAACGUAGUGGUUUCACUGAGGAACUAUGAGGCAGACAGCACUUUAACCAAUGACCAACGUCAGUGUCACUGCCCUCCUGCACCUUCUGACGGGAUACUCUGAACAGGACAUGGCAUCGCUUCUCUGUCUCAGAAAACAUAGACAGAAUUACAAAAUAAAAAAGGAUUUUGGGAGGGCUGUUUGGCUUCUGGGGGUUUGAGCCCAUCCAUGCUGCAGAGUGAAGCAGAGGAUGUCUUUGGACUAAUUUCUGCACCAAAUCAUAUCACUCAGUAAUUCUCAAAAGUGUUUCUUUAUUCCUUAUUUGCAUGUGAUUGAGGUAAUAACAGUCAAACAAGGAGACAGAUAUUUUGCAUGGAGCCUCUCACCCUAAGCAGGCUGCCAUUCACCUGAGAACACGUGGUCUUCCAGAACAUCUCUGAGGAGGCCCAGAGGGGCACCCCCAUCUGGUGCUGUCAUUGCUGAGACCUGCUUUUUUGCUAGAAAUGUGGGAUUUUUCAUAUUGGUGGAAGCCAAGCAUGCUAUAAGUAGUCAUAACUGCAAAAAGUAAGCAGAACACUGAGGAGCAGAUAGAUUAGAUCAUUUAUUUUUUUAUUGUAUUUGUUUUAUAUUCAUAAGUCUAAACAUAACACAAAACAAAAAUGAAAGGAUUAUAUUAGCCUCCUGGGGCUGCUGUAACAUGGUACCACAAGCUGGGUGUCUUGAAACAACAGGAAUUUACCCUCUCACAUCCCUGGAGGUCAGAAGUCCAAAGUCAAAGUGUCAGCAGGGCCACACUUCCUCUGCAGGCUCCGGGGACAGACCCUUCCUUGCCUCUUCCAGCUCCUGCUGCUGCCGCCGUUCUUGGCUGGUGGCUGCAUCACACCAGUCUCUGCCUGUGUGGCCACGUGGCCUCCCUUCCUGUCUCUGAGUCUUUGCGUGGCCUUCUGGUGAGGACGCCAGUCAUUGGAAUGAGGGCUCACUCUAUCUAAUAUGACCUCACCUGAGCUAAUCAUGUCUACAUGACCCUAUUUCCAAAUAAGGUCACGUUCUGAGGUUUUGGGUGGACAUGAAAUUAUGGGGGAUGAUAUUCAACCCAGUACAAAAUGAACAAAAGGAAACAUAUCAUCCAAAACAUCUGCUUUAUAAAUGAUAAAGAAAACGUAGAUAGAAUUACGAAAUAAGAAAGGACUUCGGGAGGGCUGUUUGGCUUCUGGGGGUUUGAGCCCAUCCAUGCUGCAGAGUGAAGCGUCUGCCUACCCAGAGGCCAGGCGUAUCGGGGUGACAACCAGCAAGGCAGCGGCCCGAGUGUGGCUGCCGCGGUUUAGCAAUAGUCACGGGAGCUGAAGUCAGACCUUUCAAAGAGGAAAGUCUAGCCUCCAGCCACUGCGUCCCCCAUCCCCAAGCCCCAAGUCCUAAGUACAGAAGAUGAAGAAAUGAGAGAGGAAAGACGAAUUUGGAAAUAGAAGUAGAGUUGGCCUGACACCAGCUAAAUAAAUACAGCGUUUUCCUCUUCAGUCUUUAGGAACAUUCCAGUUUGCUGUGUAAAUGGACCCUUCACCCAAUUCUACAGGACGGCUUCUGUCAGCCUGGCUACACCGUGGCAGUGACUCUUCCCAAAGGGUCUCAUUCAUUAAGGUGUCUCCCUCCACACAAGGCUGAACUAAAGGUUCCAGAGGCAUGUGCUGCCCCUUGUGUGCUCCUCAGUGUUCUCAGGGCAUCUCUAGGCGUGUGCUGUGAGCACCAGCCGGGAGUCACCCCGCAGAGGAAGGCAGGAGCCCAGAACGCAUCACCAGGGCCUGAUCACCCAAGCAGCCCUGACCAUUGGGAACGCGGUGUGUGUCGGGGCCUCAGCACUCUUCAGACCUCAGCCCGACAAAGGGAGACAGCCUUCCUUCUGGGCUGUCUGGGUGGAGAGUGGAGAUGUGAACCCACAGCCCAUAGGACAGAGCUGCUCUUCUCAAAAUCCUUCCUAGCUGGGUGAUAACACCUGUAGAACUGGCACUGUGGUUGGAGAAUCCUCCUGCAUGGAGCAGGAGAGAUGGUCCAUGGACUUGUCUGAGACUGGGGAGGUGCUGGAGGCAACUUGGCCUGAGAACUUUGUUCACCUGUUUUGAGGAGAUUGGAGAAGGAAACCCUGUACUCCAGUGAGGGCCGAUCAGGGUCACCCAUCAGCCUUACUUGCCCUAGUCAGCUCCAGCAGGUGGGGUGGAAGUGACCAGUUUGUCAAGCUGUGGGCUGGACAAGUGAGCAUUGAGGGCCGGUGAAGCCCAGUGGCCUGGAAUCUUCCUGCACCAGCAGUCGAAGGCGUGAGAAGCAGUGGUGGCCUAACAGAGAGCUUCAUCCAAAGCGCUGAGACUUUCUUUCCUUGCCAGAAAGGAUGGUUUUCAGAAACACGAGGACAGAGGCCGGGGCUUCUGGAGCAAAUCCACUGUACCCACAUAGCCUUUGUUCUUUGGGCUUUGGGAUAAAUGAUAGGCUCGCCUUUUAGGGUUUCGCUUUUUUCCCAUUUGGCCCUUGCCAUGGGCUUGGAGAGGAAGAAUUGGAGAAAGGCCAUUGGAAGAUAGUUCCCUGAUGAAGAAGAGAGCACUGGGGAAUUUCUGUCUUCAGUCAGCAGGUAUUCUGCGAGUUGGUUUGGUUUGGUUCCUUCCCCAAAGGCACAGGCAUUCCAAAGGUUGUAGUUUUGUGUCACACGGAGCCACCAACCUUUCUUUCCCACCUGAAAUAUGGCCUUUUUUUUUUUAAGAAAAAUCUGGAAAUAUUUAUUUGACCCCUACUUUAGCUGGUGACCAGAGAAGAAGGCAGCUCUGGGAUCCUAGGAUUUUAGUUACUUGUGGAAAGCUUCCCUCGGAGUAAAUCACAACAUUAAAAAUGUAGAUGCGCAGCUGGGAGAAGCAACCCCUUAUCCCAGGGACUCUCGGAAACGCUGCCUUUCUUUGUCCUGUGUAGGACGCCGCCUUAGGUAAUUAUUGAUUCAGGUUGUUGGUGGCGCCAUUUGAAGUCUCUUCCCAGGCCACAAGCAGGACAGGUUCUCCAGGGUAGGGAGAUGUGCCUAGGACACAGAAGAGCUGCCCCUCGCCUUCCACUCCUGUCAAAUACUUCUUUCUCCCAACCCAUUUUGUUGCCCCAAAAAGUAUUUUUCUAUGCGGUGGUUGAGACUCUUAGACUGGAGUUGCCCUUUGUCUUCUUUCUAAGGCACCUUCUUUUCUUCUUUCUUCCUCACACUCAUGCUGACUCUUUCGGCUGCUUUUCUCCCAGCCAAACUGAGCGAGGGGCUUUGUACCAGUGUUUCUGUCACUGGCCUAUUGAGAGCCUGCCAGCGUCACUGCCUUUUUCUCUUUGAGGGCCGUGAAAUAUUUAUAUGUCUGCCUUGCUUGUGUGCUUCUGAAAAGUUGCAUAGAAACCAAAGAGCCAAAAAUAAAUAUGAUCUUAAUUGCCCAGGAUAGCAGGCUACGCCAGAAACUUGUGGUUAGUUUUGUUGUAAACUAAACAUUUCAUCGUGCUUGUUCUGCUUUGUAAACUCAAGUGUGCAUCUCGAGUCCCAGGUUUCCCUUUGGUUACGGUUUCUUUAAAUAGAUGAAUGCUUUUGAUAUUGUGACGUAAUAAUAAGAAACAUGCUUUUGGUCUCUGGCCCUGGUUCUGGGCACACAGCUCCUACAACCUUUAGUGCUGAGUGUCUUUUUGUUUGCUAAUGAGGUGACUGUGGCGGGCCCCAGGACAACCUCCUGGGGGACUGGUUGCCAGGGCAACCGACCACGUGAUUAGAGGUUGGGACUCCACCCGUGGACCUCUGGGGAGGGGAGGGAGCCCGCAGAGGUGGAGUGGAUCACCAGUGGCCGGUGUUCUGCUCGAUCGUGCCUGUGUAAUGAGGCCUCCACAGACUCCCUCAACGACAGCGUUUGGGGGCUUGCAGGCUGCUGAGCACGGGGAGGUUCCCGGAGGGUGGAGCCCUGGCGAGGGCACAGCAGCUCCGAGCUCCCUGCCCCAUACCUCGCCCUGUGCAUCUCUUCAUCUGUACAGAGCCUUCAUUUUUAUUUUGACAUUUCUGCUGUAUGCAAGUUUUCACUUAUCUCGAAAGCCUAUCAGCAUAGUUAAGGGUGAGCUCCACAAGUACUGCACUGCUUGGGAUGAAGCUGACGUCAGGUUCAGCAGCCAGAACAGGAAGUCUGGGUCCGCUGCCCCCCACCAGCUCCCUGACAAUGAGACCGACUGUGGCUGGGCACCGUUUGAUAAGAACAACUAUCAGCAGCUGCUUGGGGCCCUGGACUACUCCUUCCUGUGCGCCUAUGCCGUGGGGAUGUACCUCAGUGGCAUCAUUGGGGAGCGCCUGCCGAUUAGGUAUUACCUAACUUUCGGGAUGCUCGCCAGCGGAGCCUUCACCGCCCUGUUCGGCUUAGGGUAUUUCUACAACAUCCACAGUUUCGGAUUCUACGUGGUAACUCAGGUCAUCAACGGGCUGGUGCAGACCACCGGCUGGCCCAGCGUCGUCACCUGCCUCGGCAACUGGUUUGGAAAAGGAAGGAGAGGUUUGAUUAUGGGGGUCUGGAACUCCCACACCUCCGUGGGCAACAUCUUGGGGUCAUUGAUCGCUGGCUACUGGGUGUCCACAUGCUGGGGCCUGUCCUUCGUCGUGCCUGGAGCCAUCGUGGCAGCCAUGGGGAUAGUGUGCUUUCUCUUCCUCAUUGAACAUCCGAACGACGUCAGGUGCUCCUCCACCCUGGUGACGCACUCAAAAGGCUAUGAGAAUGGUACAAACAGAUUGAGACUCCAGAAGCAAAUCUUGAAGAGCGAAAAGAACAAGCCUCUGGACCCAGAGAUGCAGUGCCUGCUGCUCUCAGAUGGGAAGGGCUCCAUCCACCCGAACCACGUCGUCAUUCUCCCCGGGGACGGUGGGAGUGGCACGGCCGCCAUCAGCUUCACAGGGGCCUUGAAAAUUCCAGGCGUGAUAGAGUUCUCACUGUGUCUGCUGUUUGCCAAGCUGGUCAGCUAUACUUUCCUCUUCUGGCUGCCCCUGUACAUCACGAAUGUGGAUCACCUUGAUGCCAAAAAGGCGGGGGAGCUCUCCACCCUGUUUGACGUGGGCGGAAUCUUUGGUGGGAUCCUGGCAGGUGUGAUCUCAGACCGACUGGAGAAAAGGGCCUCCACCUGCGGCCUGAUGCUGCUGCUCGCGGCCCCCACGCUCUACAUCUUCUCCACCGUCAGCAAGAUGGGGCUUGAGGCCACCAUCGCCAUGCUGCUGCUCAGCGGAGCCCUGGUCAGUGGGCCCUACACACUCAUCACCACCGCCGUCUCCGCCGACCUGGGGACUCAUAAAAGUCUGAAAGGCAACGCGCACGCCCUCUCCACCGUGACGGCCAUCAUUGACGGGACGGGCUCUGUAGGAGCAGCCCUGGGCCCCCUGCUGGCUGGGCUCCUCUCCCCGUCCGGCUGGAGCAAUGUGUUUUACAUGCUGAUGUUUGCAGAUGCCUGUGCCUUACUGUUCCUGAUCCGCCUCAUACACAAGGAGCUGAGCUGCCCAGGGUCAGCUACGGGGGACCAAGUUCCAUUUAAGGAACAGUGACACCCCACCCCAGUCCCGUGGAGGGGGUCUGGGCCCACCCUUCACAACUGCCUUUCAAGGACAGUUCAGACAAAGGGCCCUGCAUGGAAAGAGUGACCUCCCUUUGCCUUUUGCACACGCACCUGGAAAAGACACAGAAGCCAACCUGAGAACCCCUGGUGCUAUUUUAAAGGAGACAUAUUGCUGAACAGCAGUGAGAAAAGUCUGCAGGAACUGCUGCCUGAGCCAAGCCAGAGAACCGAAGACCCGGCCGGCCCUGGCCUCACAGGCGUGUGCCCAUGCAGCCACCCAAAUGCACGCGUGACAACAAGGCCGGGAGGGUGGGGGGGGUGCACAGGUAGCCCCGACCCUCUCAGGCAUUCCAGCCACAGAACAUCAAAGUGAGCGAGUACUGCGCUGGCUGUGGCUUCAGAGAACCUGUAUGUGCCACAUGGAAAAACAGGACACCAGAGCCCACCAGACAGUGCCGGCCAGCAGAGAAGCAGAGAGCCAGCGCCACACAACAUCAAGAAGGCCGACAACCAGGUUGGAAACCAAGACGGAGCUCAGACCCACCACAUCGCCCCAGAGGCUUUUCCAGCACCCAUGAUGUUUCGGACUGACCUAAAAACUAAUUGUCGAGAAGCCAAGGGUGAGGAGGCAGGAAGCACCUCCGGUUGGAGGCACCCAGGCUUGCCAGCCACAGAGCGCCCCAAAGUCACCGUCAUCCCAGCCCCUGGCCUUCCUGCUGCCCUCCGGGGCCAUGGCACUGCUGUUCAGCUCAGGCACAGGGGCACAGCAGAGGUUUGGGAAGCGGUCUCCCCACCGGCACUGGGAUUGGCGGGUCCAAGCCCAGCAACCGGCUUCGCUCCACAACACACACCACACCUGGGACUGUUUUUAAUACAUAGCAACAGACUGGGUUAUUUAUUUAAGAUGUGUAUUGUGUCAUAUGAAGUUUAAGAGACAUAAAUGGCAUUUUGUUAUUUAUUAAGACAAACUCCAAUUGUUCUCUGGCUGUUUUUUUCAGUUGUGUCUAGCAAAAUACUUAUCUGCCCUUUGAAAUAAAAUGUUUUUGUUUAAAAAA